AUGCAAACUCAGAAUCUUCUCAGUGUAACUCAGCUGAACUCACAUCUCCCAUCAACAUGUCCUACAACUGCUGCUCUGGAAACUUCUCCUCCCGCUCCUGUGGUGGCUACCUGCACUACCCAGCCUCCUCCUGUGGCUUUUCCUACCCCAGCAACCAGGUCUACAGCACUGACCUCUGCUCUCCCAGCACGUGCCAGCUGGGUUCCUCUCUCUAUAGGGGCUGUCAGCAGACCUGCUGGGAGCCCACCAGCUGCCAGACAUCCUAUGUGGAGUCCAGCCCCUGCCAGACCUCCUGCUACCGUCCCAGAACCUCCUUGCUCUGCAGUCCCUGCCAGACAACUUACUCUGGGUCUCUAGGCUUUGGAUCCAGCAGCUGCCGCUCCCUGGGCUAUGGAUCGAGGAGCUGCUACUCAGUGGGCUGUGGGUCCAGUGGCUUCAGAUCCCUGGGUUAUGGAGGCUGUGGCUUCCCUUCCCUGGGCUAUGGCGUUGGAUUCUGCCGCCCAACCUACUUGGCUUCUAGGAGCUGCCAGUCUUCUUGCUACAGACCAACUUGUGGAUCAGGCUUCUACUAUUGAUCAUCUUGUUAAAUUGCUGAUUUUGUUGGCUAAUGCCUUCAAUGCCUCUACUCAUAACCUUUAUUGUCUUCAUCAUGUACAGAAAGAAUUAGCCUCUUAUUCUAUAAUUAUCAAGUUCUCAGUUUGUCUUUGUCCCCAAAUACUGGCUGGCAGGCUUCAUCUGAAAAACUGUAAUUGGAGAACUAGCUCAAAAUAAAUCUUGAAAUACACAUUAAAA